AGUGGGGUCACGUGUUGCGCGCGAGCCACCUCCCCUGCUGGCGCUUCCUGUCGCUACCGCUGCGGCCCAGGGCCCGCGGGAGCCCAGGGCGGUGCCGGGUGAGACAAGGCCGGGGUUUGGCUCGGAUUCACCGCGAGGUAUCUAGGCUGCCAUGAUGCCAGGGCCAAGACCUCGGAAGGGCCCUCAGGCCAGAGGCCAAGGGGUGGCCGCUGCCAAGCAGAUGGGGCUCUUUAUGGAGUUUGGCCCUGAGGACAUGCUGCUGGGCAUGGAUGAGGCUGAAGAUGAUGAGGACCUGGAGGCUGAGCUGCUGGCUCUCACAGGGGAAGCACAAACCACAGGCAAGAAGCCAGCACCCAAGGGGCAGGCCCCCCUGCCCAUGGCCCACAUCGAGAAGUUGGCGGCAGACUGUAUGCGGGAUGUGGAGGAGGAGGAGGAGGAGGAAGGGCUGGAGGAAGAUGCAGAGCUGCUGACGGAGCUGCAGGAGGUCUUAGGUGUGGACGAGGAGACUGAGCCCCUGGAUGGUGAUGAGGUAGCUGACCCAGGCGGCUCUGAGGAGGAGAACGGCCUAGAAGACACUGAACCUCCAGUGCAGACAGCCGUCCUGACAGCUUCAGCCCCAGCAGCUCAGGCCGGAGCAUCUCAGGGGCUACACGCUUUGCUGGAGGAACGGAUUCACAACUACCGAGAGGCUGCGGCCAGUGCCAAGGAGGCAGGCGAAGCAGCCAAAGCCAGGCGCUGCGAGCGCGGCCUGAAGACCUUGGAGUCGCAGCUAGCCUCUGUGAGGAGAGGCAGAAAGAUCAAUGAGGAUGAGAUCCCACCUCCAGUGGCCUUAGGAAAGCGGCCCCUGGCCCCCCAGGAACCAGCCAACAGGAGCCCUGAGACAGACCCUCCAGCUCCCCCUGCCUUGGAGUCAGACAACCCCUCCCAACCUGAGACCAGCCUCCCUGGCAUUUCUGCCCAGCCCGUUUCAGACUUAGACCCAGACCCGCGGGCCCUGCUGUCAUCCCGACAGAGAGAGUACAAAGUGGCUGCCCUCAGUGCCAAGCGGGCUGGAGAGCUAGACCGUGCCCGAGAGCUCAUGAGGAUUGGGAAGAGAUUCGGUGCUGUCCUGGAGGCCCUGGAGAAGGGGCAGCCCGUGGAUCUGAGUGCCAUGCCCCCGGCACCUGAGGAUCUGAAGCCCCAGCAGGCUUCUCAGGCUCCCACAGCACCCUCAGUCAUUCCCCCAGCCGUGGAGCGAGUGCAGCCAGUGAUGGCCCCUGACGUCCCAGCAACCCCAGUGGCCCCUACAGAGUCACAGACAGUGCUGGAUGCCCUGCAGCAGAGGCUGAACAAGUACCGCGAGGCGGGCAUCCAGGCCCGGAGUGGUGGGGACGAGCGCAAGGCUCGGAUGCAUGAGCGCAUUGCCAAGCAAUAUCAAGAUGCUAUUCGAGCACACCGAGCAGGACGGAAAGUCAACUUUGCUGAAUUGCCUGUUCCUCCAGGAUUUCCCCCCAUCCCUGGCCUGGAGUCCACUAUGGGUGUUGAGGAGGACGCAGUGGCAGCGACAUUGGCAGCUGCAGAGAAACUGGCCUCUGCAGAGGAUUCAGCCCCGGCUGAUAAAGACGAGGACGAGCCUCCUGGGCACCUGCAGGGUGAGCCCCCAGCACAGGCCCCAGUGGCCAAGAAACCUGCACGGCCCACAGUCCCUUCAUCCCAGCGCCUGCCUGAGCCCAGGGCCUCAAGUUCUAAGGAGUCACCGAGUCCAUCUGUGCGGGAGCAGCUGGCACUGCUGGAGGCACGGAAACUGCAGUAUCAGCGGGCAGCCCUGCAGGCCAAGCGCAGCCAGGACCUGGAGCAGGCCAAAGCCUAUCUGCGGGUAGCCAAAUGGCUUGAGGCUCAGAUCAUCCAGGCCCGAUCUGGCAGACCUGUUGAUCUGUCCAAGGUGCCUUCGCCCUUGACGGAUGAGGAGGGUGACUUCAUCCUCAUCCACCAUGAGGACCUGCGACUCUCCCAGAAGGCGGAGGAGGUGUAUGCCCAGCUGCAAAAAAUGCUUCUGGAGCAACAAGAGAAGUGCCUGCUGUUCUCCAAGCAGUUCAUGCACCAGGGCAACGUGGCUGAGACCACCCGAUUUGAGAAGCUUGCUCAGGACCGCAAGAAACAGCUGGAGAUCCUGCAGCUGGCCCAGGCUCAGGGCCUCGACCCUCCCACCCACCACUUUGAGUUGAAGACAUUCCAGACUGUGAGGAUCUUCUCAGAACUCAACAGCACAGAAAUGCAUCUGAUCAUUGUCCGGGGAAUGAACCUCCCAGCCCCUCCAGGGGUGACUCCCGAUGACCUGGAUGCUUUUGUGCGGUUUGAGUUUCACUACCCUAACUCGGACCAGGCUCAAAAAAGCAAAACAGCUGUGGUGAAGAACACAAACUCUCCAGAAUUUGAUCAACUCUUCAAACUAAACAUCAACCGAAACCACCGGGGCUUCAAGAGGGUGAUCCAGAGCAAAGGCAUCAAGUUUGAGAUCUUCCACAAAGGGUCCUUCUUCAGAAGCGACAAGCUGGUUGGCACAGCACACCUGAAACUGGAGCGGCUGGAGAAUGAGUGUGAGAUCAGAGAAAUUGUGGAGGUCCUGGAUGGAAGGAAGCCCACCGGGGGGAAGCUGGAGGUGAAGGUGAGGCUGCGGGAGCCUCUGAGUGGCCAGGAUGUGCAGAUGGUCACUGAGAACUGGCUGGUUCUGGAGCCCAGGGGCUUGUGAGGUGGGCAGCUCUCUGGGCCUUCAGAACCUUUGCCCCCUCCUUUUACUCAACUAACUACUCAACUCAUAUCUGGAGAGAAAACCUAGGAGUUUCUCAUCUAUGAGAAAGACCUACCAUGCUGGGUAGGGCUUAUGGGCUGAGUUUCUGAUGUUCCUCAGUAGAACUGGGAAGAGAAGGUAACCUUCCAAGGUUUAACUAUCUAUCUAUCUAUCUAUCUUCAGGAAACCCUUUCUAAAAUCUUUGUGUUUUCACUGCAGUUUAGACUGACUUCUUGUGCUUUGCACCCCUGUGUAGCCGAUGGCCAGCACCAGGAGAGGAGUCAGGCCGCGACUGUGCAGGAGAUGACUUUCCCAGCUUUGCUGGCUUCAGAAGCCUUUGUACAUAAGAGAUGCUGCUACCCAAGCACCAAAGACCUGUUAAGCAUGUGCACUACUGACCACGACUCUGGUCUUUCCUGUUGUUGGCCCCUCUGGGGCUCUACAGAAACAGGCUGGGUUCCAGGAGCCCAUCUCCCCGCUGUCUCCCCCUGCCCCGAGUCUGGAAGAGGGCAAGGACACUUCCAUUCCUCUGUACCAUGGAGUCCUGCAGCCCCUUAACCCCUGCGUGGCAACUGUGUACAGCUUACCCCUGCCUCCAGUUGCACCACUUCUAGAUGUGCCUUUAAAAGAUCUAACUAUGGGAUGGGAGAACUUGAGGGUGAUCGGGAACCUCCCCUGCUGAGGGUGGUGUCAGGGUUCCGUGACUCCAGUGGGCCAGUGGUAGCCUGUCCCAGACAACUCCGUCACCCCAGCUCUGCCUGUGCCUUUAUCCCUGACAGCUGCUGCACUAGCCUUCCUGCUUCCCUAAGGACUUAGUGGAGGGGGAAAGUUGUUUUUGGUACUACUUGGUGGGAAGUAAGGGGAAGGUUGGAUCUUGGGUUUGGUCUACCCACCCAAGAGAAAAGACUGUUAACUGGAAGAAAAAAUAUAUAUAUAAAAUUUUAUGUAGACACGUUUAUUUAUCUAGGAAACUAAGUCUAACUCAUUGUAGGGAUUUUAUACUCAACUAUACAGAGUAUCCACCAAAGUCCUAAUCUAAAGUCCUGCUCCCUGUCACUUUUUAAAAGCCAGGGUAGCAGUAACAUGACAAACGGCUGCUGUGGCUUCCUCUUGAGAGAGGACAGGGAAAGCCUUUCCUCUUCGGCUGGUUAUGUGGGGAACUUCCUUAGUUUUUUUCCACAAGAAAUUCUCCUUUGGCUUUGUUUUUCUGAAUGGAUGGAGACUAUGAAGGGGUUUGUAGUUGUAAGAGAUUUAAUAUUCAAAACUGAAAUAUUCUGCAUUUCUUAGAAAUACCCCAUCUUCCCCCACCCCCUUUUUGAAUUAUUAAUUCAAGAUCAACAAAGCAUUCCUCAAGAUCACUUUUAAAAAAGGUUAGAAGUGAAGCAAAUACAUUCAGCUUACUGAUCACUAUAGUAUUGCAUAAGCACAGCUCAAGAACUGAGCUUUGUAUGUGUCCUUUUGGGGGAUAACAGGGCUGGACCAUGCUUCCCUGCCCUUAAACGCAGAGCUUUUAGUGGGUCACAGAGCGGGAACUACACACAAGUGACUUUUUUCCCCAUGAGCCCUCUGGCCGAUUUUUUUUUUUUUUUUUUUUUUGAGACAGAGUAGCUCUCUGCCAGCCAGGCUGGAGUGCAGUGGCAUGAUCUCAGCUCGCUGCAACCCCCACCUCCCAGGUUCAAGCGAUUCUCCUGUGUCAGUCUCCUGAGUAGCUGGGAUUACAGGCACCCACCACUAUGCCCAGCUAAUUUUUUUAUUUUUAGUAGAGACGGUGUUUCACCAUGUUGGUCAGGCUGGUCUCGAACUCCUGACCUCAUGAUCCACCCACCUCAGCCUCCCAAAGUGCUGGGAUUACAGGUGUGAGCCACCGCACCCGGCUGGCCAAUCUUAUCAGAAGUGAGCUACCAAAACUUCCACAGAUGUGAGAUUUAACACUUAAUUGCAGUCACGUGUAUGCAACACAGCAAUAAUCUAGAAUGAAAAGGAGGGUGAUUAGCCUUCAUAAGAUGACCUAUAGAGCAAAGAAAGGUGACUGGAAGGGUUCCUAACCCAACCUACUCCCCUUAGGGUGUGUAUCCAACCCAGUGCUUCCUAAGAGGGUUACGGACCACUGUGGUUAUCCUCUAAAGUUCCAGCCAGCUCUAGGAGUUUCUAAAUUCAGGCCUCUGUUGGAAAUGGCCUAUUUCGAUAGAUAGAAAGUUUUCUAUAGCUCUAAAGGUUUCUCCUUUGCAACCCAUUCAAUUUCAGUCUGCUGCUUUGCUCUUUCAAAACAGAACCUCCAGGCUGACGAGGCAAGACAAAGCCUCCCACCAGACUUGGAGAUUGAAGUUCUUAAAAGGCCUUUGUUGUAGCCAAAGGCAUGCAUGCGUCACUGGUAGUAGGAGGAGCCUGUCCCAGCUUCAUCUUGUCCUGAGAUUUAUCCACAUACAGGAAACAGGCGGGACACAGUGGCUCACGCCUGUAAUCCCACCACUUUGGAAAGCUGAGGCAGGUGGAUCACCUGAGGUCAGGAAUUCAAGACCAGCCUGGCCAACAUGGUGAAACCCCGUCUCCACUAAAAACAAAAACAAUUAGCUGGGCAUGGUGGCCGGCGCCUGUAAUCCCAGCUACUAGGGAGGCUGAGACACACGAAUCCCUUGAGCCCAGGAAGCAGAGGUUGCAGUGAGCCUCGAUUGUACCACUGCACUCCAGCCUGGGCGACAGAGCAAGACUCUGUCUCAAAACAAACACAAAUACAGUAUCCAAACAUUGGAGAUUAGUGACUCACCUGCAGUUGGGAGCCAGCUACAACCCAAAUCAUUUUAAAAUUUUCAAUUCUUUGAUCUCAUGCAAUGCACACUUUCUUCUGAAUUAGCAAACUGAAUAAACUACAGAAAUUUUUUAGAA